GCGUCUUUGUUGUUGGCGACCGGGAUCCCUUCUCGGCACAGGGGAAAGGCGGGGAAGCCACUCCUCAUCGGGUCUGUGUUUUUGAGAGGAUUCUCUGAUGGUUGCGUGAAGGGGAGCGGUAGGACAGUCCCUGCGGUCCGUGGAGCGGCCGGAGUCAGGGGGUGGGGGAGGGAGGACCGACCGACACUCUAAGAAGGUCUUUGGUCCUCCUCGGUGAAGAGAAGGGUUCCAUUUCAUUUCCUUUGCUUUUCUCUCAGUGGAUGAAAAGAUGGGGUCAGGUUCCCAUUCCCCUCACUGGCGCACUGAGAGAUUCGCGGGUGCCUAAAAGCUUUCUCCUGAAUGUCCUUAUAUCUCUGUCGGGCGCGAUUUUAGAUUGAAUCUGCACGGGGCUUGGCGAUUUGUGUAUUCCGGUGGGGCUGUCGUAGGGUUCUUUUUCUUUAGAUGGUUGGGCUUUAAUCUUAUUUGUUUUCGAACUCUAAGGUAGGCUUAUCAGGAAUCGUUUUUGAAUUGGAAAAUUUAAAGGUUUUGUUUGGGAUUUUUUUUAACCCCGAAACAAAGUUAUGUCAAAUUAGAUUGUACUGUGUGGGGGCUCUCGUGAAGGAAAGAGUGUAUUUAACCUGGGGUUUUUGUUUAAAAAAAAAAAAAGUUCAGAUCUUUGAUCUUUGGUGAGAUCUCUGCCAAUGCCAGAAGAGAAUUUUUUGUAAAUGAUGCUUUAAGUCAGUGUGAAGUAGAUUUGGUAAGCAAAAGGAUGAAUAACGGAAUACAGAGGGUGACCUUUAAAUUUCGCUGUUUAUGAAAUGUGUUCCUGUUUAAUACUUUUUGUGAUAUAUGAUGCUUGAUCUAUAGAUGAUUCAUUUGGAAUUUUUUUAUGCCUCUAAUAAAUCUUUGGAGAUCUUGUGCCAACAUAUGAAACUAUAAUACCUAAUGAGUCGGAGUAGAAAGCCAGAUACAUGUUGUAAUAACGUUAAUCUGUUUAGAUUAACAGGGAAAUUUACAUUAAAAUGAACUUUUUUCCGUAAAGAGUUUCUCUACAUAUGUUUAUAGCAUGAAUUUCAGUUGGGUGACAUCUAAUGAUAGCCAGUAUUUUGAAAAUUGUCAUGAUUGCUAGUAUUCUAAUUUGAGACUGCUCAACUUGUUGGUAAGUUUUUAUUUGGAGAAUAGGGGUCGUGUUACUUAAGGAACAGCAGAGGUAAAAAUCUCUGUUGUGCAGUAAUUGUCAUAUCAUUUGAAAUCCAGAAGGAAAUGAAUGGCACCUUCACCUAUAUUUUGACCUCUCUUUUCUCCUACUCUAGUGUUAAUAAGGUUAAUUGGCAAGGACAGGAUUAGAUUUUUAGCAGGCUAGGCAGUUUUAAUUUUGUCCCUUAGUGUGCAGUAUUCUAGUUGAUGAGUAGCUUGUUUCCUUGAGUAUCUUUGCCCAUUUUGAAAUGUUUAUGAAAUGACUGCUGACAAAGAAUUUUCUGUUUCCUGGGACAAACAAAAUCACCAAAAAACAUCAUGAAAAAAUAAUGUUUUUAGUAGCUUAAUGAACACAGAAGAAUUAAGCAAUUAGUGUCUGUUCCAAGUUUGACACUGAAUUGGUCUACAACUCCAGGCACGCUAUCCCACAUCUGAGUCAGUUUUCUCCAUCUGUAAUAUAGGGCUGAUAAAAUGUGCCACCUGCUCACUUUAUAAAAAGGGGAGUGAGAACCAUGUAAGCAACAGUUACUCUGGUUAUGUGACAUUGAUAUAAGUUAAAUGAGAAUACUUUUUAAUGCAGUGCUCUUACUUUGUUUUGAUAUUAUGAAUUUCAAUCAUUUGAUGAACAGUUAGCAUAAAGAUAAGGAGAAUGACUCUCCCUAUGCCAUCAUUUAAGAAUUAAAAUUUCUUCCGUAUUAAGAUUGGUGUUAAGAUCUUUAGAAGCAGUGAUGACAAGAAAAUAGAGUAUAUUUUAUUGGUUGGUUUAUUUACUGGUAGAUUUUACUUCUGAUUUAUCCAAAGUUUUGCUCUUAAUUCUGAAAAUUCCCCCUACCCUUCCUACUCUUUAAAAUUUCUCACAUACAUUGCCCCAUUUGCCUGUCGAAUCCAGCCUUGUGAGUUGGAGAGAGGGAAGGUGAGUUUGUGGCCUUUUUUUUUUUUUUUUUUUUUGAGACGGAGUUUUGCUCUUGUUGCCCAGGCUGGCGUGCAAUGGCGCGAUCUCGGCUCACUGCAACCUCUGCUUCCCGGGUUCAAGUGAUUCUUCUGCCUCAGCCUCCUGAGUAGCUGGGAUUACGGGCACCCGCCACCACUCCCGGCUAAUUUUUUGUAUUUUUAGUAGAGAUGGGGUUUCACCACGUUGGCCAUGCUGGUCUUCAACUCCUGACCUCAGGUGAUCCACCCGCCUUGGCCUCCCAAAGUGCUAGGAUUACAGGUGUGAGCCACUUCACUGUUUGUGGAAUUUUUACAGAUGAAAUAAAUAAAGCCCAGAUAAGUUAAUUAUUUCAAUUGCCUAAAGCUAAGCAAUUAGUAAGAAGUAGAAUUGAGGCUUGAACUUGGGUCUUCUCUAGUCCUGAAUCCUUUGCUUUGGAGCAGUGUUUUCCAAACACCUGUUCAUGCCCAAGAGUUUUGUCCAAGUGAAGUGAGAACUAACAUAGCAAUAUAAAUGUUGGUGCCAUACAAUAUAAUGAAUAUCCAUGUACCCAUCACCCAGUUAAACAAACAAAACUACCAAUUAAAACGAAGUGUCCGGCCAGGCUCGGUGGCUCACGCCUGUAAUCCCAGCACUUUGGGAGGGAGGCCGAGGCAGGCGGAUCACCUGGGGUCGGGAGUUAGAGACCAGCCUGACCAACAUGGAGAAACCCCGUCUCUACUAAAAAUACAAAAUUAGCCGGGUGUGGUGGUGCUUGCCUGUAAUCCCAGCCACUCGGGAGGCUGAGGCAGGAGAAUCGCUUGAACCCAGGAGGCAGAGGUUGUGGUGAGCCAAGAUAGCACCAUUGCACUCCAGCGUGGGCAGCAAGAGCAAAACUCUGUCUCAGAAAAACAAAAACAAAAAACGAGGUUUCCUUAGUAUGUUAAUACCUCUCUUAAAUGCUGUUCCCUUUUCCCCCCGAUAUCUAACCAGUGACCCAAAGUUGACAUGCAUCCUUCCUAUAUCCACGUGUUGAUACUUAACUACAUACCUUUAUCCUAUGAACAUUAUAUAUAUAUAGUUUUAUUUUGAUUGUCUUAAGACUAUUUAAAUACAGAUAUCUUUAUUUAGCUUGCUUUCUUCACACAACUUGGCCAAGAUUUAUCUAUGUUUAUUUAGGUAGCUCUAGUUUAUUUACUUUUACUGUUAGGUGGUAUGUGCUCUGUUAUAUAACUAUGUCAGGUUUCUGUUGAUGGUCAUUUUUGUUGUUUCCAUUUGUUUGCUAUUAAACAGUACUAUAAGGAAUAUUCCUGUAUAUGUUAGGUAUCUGUUGUGUAAGACUUCUAGAGCAGUGGUUCUUGACCCUACCUACAUCCCAUGUUCAUAGAAAAUAUUUUACAGUACUUUAAAGAAAGCAUUGGCCUUAAUAAAAUAAGAAAAAAUUGUAAUAAAGUAAUAUGUGUUUCACUUUGUAAAUACUCGAGCUCAAGACUACAUUCAAGAUUAGCCACCAAGUGUAAUGGUCGACCAGCAACAUCAGAAUCCCUUGGGAGCUUGUUGGAAAUGCAGAGCAUCAGACUUUAACCUACUGAUGCAGAUGCUGUUUUUUUUUUUGUUUGUUUGUUUGUUUUUUAAUAAUGUAAAAGACAGGAUCUCUGGAGCCAUACAACUCACUGUAACCUCAAACUCCUGGGCUCAAGGGAUCCUCCCACUUCAGCCUCCUGAGCAUCUGGGACUACAGGUAUGCACCAUCAAGCCUGGCUAAUUUUUAGAUUUUUUACAGAGACAGGGUCUUGCUAUCUUGCCCAGGCUGAUCUUGAACUCCUGGCCUCAAGUGAUCCUCCCUCCUCAGUAUCCCAAAGCACUGGGACAUUGGGAUUACAGACAUGAGCCACUGUGCCCGGCCAGAUGCUGUAUUUUAUCAAGAUUCCCAGGUGAUGCAUAUACGCAUUGAAAUAUAAGAAGCACUGCUAAAAGAAAUAGUAGUAAUUAGACGCUUUGUACCAAUGGAUGGUGUCUCCAUCAAUACAACAGCUACAGAUUAAAACAGAGCAUGAAUAAUCUUUCAUUUAGUGAGCUAUGUUGCCUCUUCUGCUGUCCACCUUGUCCAGGGAAGAUUGCUUCAAAAUUAGCGUUUUUGCCACCUGAUCCAACUUACACACUGAUGUGUGAUGAAAGCGGAAGCCGUUGGACUUUACAUCUGUCUGAACGAGCAGACUGGCAGUAUUCUUCUAGAGAAAAAGAUGCUAUUGAGUGUUUCAUGACUAGAACCAGUAAAGGCAACAGAAUUGCUUGUAUGUUUGUACGUUGUUCACCCAAUGCGAAAUACACUUUACUCUUCUCACAUGGAAAUGCUGUUGAUCUUGGUCAAAUGAGCAGCUUUUACAUAGGACUAGGAUCACGGAUUAAUUGUAAUAUAUUCUCAUAUGAUUAUUCUGGAUAUGGUGCCAGUUCCGGGAAACCCACAGAGAAGAACCUCUAUGCAGACAUUGAAGCUGCUUGGCUUGCUCUUAGGACAAGAUAUGGCAUUCGCCCUGAAAAUGUGAUUAUAUAUGGCCAAAGUAUAGGGACAGUACCGUCUGUGGAUCUUGCUGCUCGAUAUGAGAGUGCUGCUGUUAUUCUUCAUUCUCCUCUGACUUCGGGAAUGCGAGUUGCCUUUCCUGAUACCAAGAAGACCUACUGUUUUGAUGCAUUCCCAAACAUUGACAAAAUCUCUAAGAUAACCUCUCCAGUAUUAAUAAUUCAUGGGACUGAAGAUGAAGUCAUUGACUUUUCACAUGGCCUCGCAUUGUUUGAACGUUGCCAAAGACCUGUGGAGCCUCUCUGGGUUGAAGGAGCAGGUCACAAUGAUGUGGAACUUUAUGGACAGUAUCUUGAAAGGUUGAAACAGUUUGUGUCACAGGAACUGGUGCAGAAACAUAAAGAAGGGAAGUGAUUUUCUCAAGGUCUACAGUUUUCAAUGACGGUACUAUGUAUUCCAUUAUCUUCUCUUUACCAAACUUAACUGGAUUAAUAUACCAAUGAUCCUUUCAAAUUAUAUGACAUAAACUUAUUUGCUCUCCAA